AGCUGCCAUCAGAGCCCUGCCCAAAGGGAGCUGGCCUUCCCACUUCGUGCUCCUGUGCUGGGGACCUGGGACACCAGCACCCUCCCCACCCCAGCCAGUGCUUUCCUCCUGGCCCAUGGGGACGCUGGUGGCCAAGCUGCUCCUGCCCACCCUCAGCAGCCUGGCCUUCCUCCCCACUGUCAGCAUCGCGGCCAAGAGGCGGUUCCACAUGGAGGCCAUGGUCUACCUCUUCACCCUGUUCUUCGUGGCGCUCCACCAUGCCUGCAAUGGACCCGGCUUGUCUGUGCUGUGCUUCAUGCGUCACGACAUCCUGGAGUAUUUCAGUGUCUACGGGACAGCCCUGAGCAUGUGGGUCUCGCUGAUGGCACUGGCCGACUUCGACGAACCCAAGAGGUCAACAUUUGUGAUGUUCGGCGUCCUGACCAUUGCUGUGCGGAUCUACCAUGACCGAUGGGGCUACGGGGUGUACUCGGGCCCCAUCGGCACAGCCAUCCUCAUCAUCGCGGCAAAGUGGCUACAGAAGAUGAAGGAGAAGAAGGGCCUGUACCCAGACAAGAGCGUCUACACCCAGCAGAUAGGCCCCGGCCUCUGCUUCGGGGCGCUGGCCCUGAUGCUACGCUUCUUCUUUGAGGACUGGGACUACACUUAUGUCCACAGCUUCUACCACUGUGCCCUGGCUAUGUCCUUUGUUCUGCUGCUGCCCAAGGUCAACAAGAAGGCUGGAUCCCCGGGGACCCCGGCCAAGCUGGACUGCUCCACCCUGUGCUGUGCUUGUGUCUGAUGCUGCGCCCAGCCCGGCUCUGAGCCCCUGCCCUCCCCAGCUCACACUUG